ACUCCGGCCCGCUAGACCUGCUGCUAUGUCCCGGCCGCAGCUUCGACGCUGGCGCCUCGUCUCUAGCCCGCCGAGCGGCGUCCCGGGUCUAGCGCUGCUGGCGCUGCUGGCGCUGCUGGCGCUGCGGCUCGCGGCCGGGACCGACUGCCCAUGCCCGGAGCCUGAGCUCUGCCGCCCGAUUCGCCACCAUCCAGAUUUCGAGGUCUUUGUGUUUGAUGUUGGACAGAAAACUUGGAAAUCUUAUGAUUGGUCACAGAUUACAACUGUGGCAACAUUUGGAAAAUAUGACUCAGAACUUAUGUGCUACGCUCAUUCAAAAGGAGCCAGAGUAGUACUUAAAGGAGAUGUAUCCUUAAAGGAUAUCAUUGAUCCUGCUUUCAGAGCAUCCUGGAUAGCUCAAAAACUUAAUUUGGCCAAAACACAAUAUAUGGAUGGAAUUAAUAUAGAUAUAGAGCAAGAAGUUAAUUGUUUAUCACCUGAAUAUGAUGCAUUAACUGCUUUAGUCAAAGAAACUACAGACUCUUUCCAUCGUGAAAUUGAGGGAUCACAGGUAACCUUUGAUGUAGCUUGGUCUCCAAAGAACAUAGACAGAAGAUGCUAUAAUUAUACUGGAAUCGCAGAUGCUUGUGACUUCCUCUUUGUGAUGUCUUAUGAUGAACAAAGUCAGAUCUGGUCAGAAUGUAUUGCAGCAGCCAAUGCUCCCUAUAAUCAGACAUUAACUGGAUAUAAUGACUACAUCAAGAUGAGCAUUAAUCCUAAGAAACUUGUAAUGGGUGUUCCUUGGUAUGGUUAUGAUUAUACCUGCCUGAAUCUGUCUGAGGAUCAUGUUUGUACCAUUGCAAAAGUCCCUUUCCGGGGGGCUCCUUGUAGUGACGCUGCAGGACGUCAGGUGCCCUACAAAACGAUCAUGAAGCAAAUAAAUAGUUCUAUUUCUGGAAACCUAUGGGAUAAAGAUCAGCGGGCUCCUUAUUAUAACUAUAAAGAUCCUGCUGGCCACUUUCAUCAAGUAUGGUAUGAUAACCCUCAGAGUAUUUCUUUAAAGGCAACAUAUAUACAAAACUAUCGCUUACGGGGCAUUGGCAUGUGGAAUGCAAACUGUCUUGACUACUCUGGAGAUGCUGUAGCCAAACAGCAAACUGAAGAAAUGUGGGAAGUCUUAAAGCCAAAGCUGUUACAGAGAUGAACAUCUUUUGUCAAACCAUUAAGAGUUAGAAAGAUGAUCUGUAUCAACAGAUCUAGUUUCUUGCAUUUUUAUUAUGUUGCUAUAUACUUUUGUUAUCCGUAUACUAAAAAAAAAGAAUAAAUAAAUGUUUUGAUUGUUUGAAUUUGAAAAAUACACACGAAUGUCCUCAGUAUCCAGGAACAUAAAGGCAAGAAGCAAGUCAACUUACCUAUUAAAUAUUCCUCUAUUAGAUGUUUCAACACUAUAAUUUAAUUGGGAAAAAUUGCUUUCAGAAUUUUAUUAUGCCAUAUUUCCCUUCAUUAUAGUAAAAUAUAUGCUCACGAAUCAAUGCUGAUUUUUAAAAUAUGUAUAAUCUGAAGUGGAAAUUGUUUGCUUAGAGUUUUUAAAAACCUAGUCUUUGAAAAGCAGUUUGUGCUAUACUUUUCCCCCAACCCUCCAAUAAAUCUUAAAUUUAAAACCUACAAUGUAGUGUCUCCCCUUUAGGUUCAUCAAACUGAUGAAAAUAAUUUUUCUGCUUCCUGACUCCAUAUAGUAUUUAUGUUCUCUGAGGUACUUGAACUAAAUCUUUGGACAGUGAGUGAGAAUUAAAAAGAAUCCAGAAGAUUAAAUGUAUUCACAAAAUAGAAGAAUGUAACAGUAAUAUUUUGAAUUGGUAAGUUAGAACUACCUAAUAUUUUCCAACUACAUUAUUUUUAUGAGGCUCAUUUGUAAAAUUUUUAAUAAUAGGAAUAACUUGCAGUUGAACUUGAUUCUGUUCACUGUCACACUUCUAAUUAUUCAUUUCUUCAUUUAUGGACAUAUAUAAUUUAUUUCUUGGCUAGCUUGCUUACAUGGUUAAAUUUUUCUUUCUACAUCUGCAAUGUAUCUUUUUUAUUUUUAUUUUUUGUAGAGACAGGGUCUCGCUAUGUUGUCCAGAUGGGUCUCCAACUCCUGGGCUCAAGCACUCCUCCUGCCUUGGCUUCCUAAAGAGCUGGGAUUACAGGCAUGAGCUGCAUUGUGCUUUUAAUGAUCUAAAGACACUGAUUAGCUUCUCAACUAGUUCUCUUUCUAAAAGAUCAAUUUUAUACAAAUAAGUUUUCUAAAUGUAAUAAAGUCUGUUUUCUUUCUCCAGGGAAUUAAGAACAACAUUGUGCUGCCCUUAUUAGUUCCUAAUUACAGAUUAAAAAUCUGUAUCUUUGAACUCUAGAUUUACAUAAAUCCUGGCUUCCCUGCACAUUUUGCCCCUGUAAAUUGGAAUACAUGAUGAUUGAACCAUCUGUUAUGAGAAUAUUACAUUUCCUAUUUACACAAUUGUUUGUGACAGAGUAAAAACCAUUUUCAUAGUAUAUGUUGGAUCACUGUUGUCUUCAUAUUUCUAAAAUAAAUGAAUUAAAAAAUUUAAAUUCUUAGAUGCUUAUCUCUAUCAUAGCUCAGAAUGCAACUUCAAUACCCCCAUUCUUUUAUAUUUCCAGAUUUCUUUUAAUUAAGAUAUAAUGAACAAAUUAAGUUAAAUGAAGUCUGUAUUUUCAUGCAAAUAUAUUAGUAUUCAUUAAUAUACAUUUAUUCUUUGCAAAUAGAUUUUAGUUAUAUUAGCUCUUAAAUUGUUAAAUAAAUUAUUAUUGAAUUUUAUUAUUAAAUUAUUAAAAUGAAAAUUAUAAAAUUAGCACUGUAAAAUAAUAUGUAAAGGACUUGGAAUGUUAAAAAUAACCAUUCAUCAUUUUGCUUUAUAUUACAUCUAAUAUUUCCUGAAACAUUUUGUAAUACCCACAUGGAAAGUGGAGAAAGAGAAACCUUGUGCUUUUUAUAAAACAUUGCCAAGGAGAAUAAUGGUUAAACAAAUCUGUUCAAAUACAUAUUUAAAUUUUUUUACAAAUAAAAGUUUUAAAUUAACAUACCUAAUUGAGAUUGUAGAGAUGUAUUAUUUUUUUUUUCUGUGCCAGUUCAGUUUUCAAUGUUCGUAAAUCUGAAACUGCUUGUUUUCUCAUCUAUAAAAAGAAUUACUUUUCAAAAAUGAACUUCAUCAUACCCUUCUAAAAGUACAUCAUAGUUGUCAUGUAAACAGGGUUUUUGUAACCGCUUUAACUGUCUUCUCUCAUUUGGCUUCAGUGCUUUCAACUCCCACUGGAUUACUACAGUAAAUGUGUAGAUUAUGAAUGCUGUUUAAUAAGCAUGCUUAUCUACUGGUGAGAUAUGCUAUAAGGUAACCUUGUUUAUGAGUAGAUAGGGACAAUACAAUUGAACUGUUCUAAAAACUAGAGUGAGAAAGAAUUUUAUGUUUUGCUUAAACUUCAAAACCUGUUGUUCUCAAUGUGUAAAGAAAAUAGUGAAAACAACAAGAAAACAAAAUACAAAAAAAACCCUUAAUUCCUAGCCCUUAGGAACGGAAUAGAUAUUUCAGAAAUAUAGUGUUUACUCUGUGGCAAGCACUCUUCUAAGUGUAUUAGUCUCUUAUUUUUUUUUCAAAAAUUUUACAGAAUCAGAUACUAGUAUUUAUCCCCAUUUUACAGUUGAAAUGGAGACCUUUAGAGGCUAAGUAACUUGCUCAAGAUAAAAAACUAGUAAGUGAAGUGGGUACAGCCAGGAUUCAAAUUCAAACCACCUGGUACCAGAGCCCUUACUAUUCCAAGUGUUGUCUGUGGACAGCAGCAUUAGCAUCAGUUGGGAGCUUGUUAGGUAGGAAGAAUCUCAGGCUGCACCCAGACCUACUGAGUCAGAUCCUGCAUUUUUAAACAGGAUCCUCAGAUGAUAUAUUAAACUUUGAGAAGCACUACUUAUGCUAUACUAUCUUGAAUAAAUAUGGUUGCAAGAGACUCAGGCUGGGUUUUUUUUGUCCCUUAGUUCUGAAUCUUAUAGGUAGUGCUGUUUUGGGGAGAUCAUUCAGAAAUCAAUAAAACUUCUUAAAUAAUGUCUGUUAUGUGUCAAUCAGGCACUAUGGUUAAAUACAGGAUUUUUUCCCCCCAGCCUAUAAGCUGAAAACUUUGUUCUCUUUUUUUCCUCUUAUUCCACUUGUCCUUACUGUUUUUGUAUGAACAAUUCUAAUUUGAGUUCAAACCAUGAGUGACAUUUGUAAUGUUAAAAUAUACAAAGAUUACAAGUAAUGUGCAUGCUUUCCAGAAGAAAACAGCAUGAGGGGAGUCAUAAUCCAAGCCUCUGGGGGCAUUUUUAUUACUCCUUCCUACCUACCCAAUUAUUAAGUGUACAAGUUUACAUAUUGGCUUUAUCUCCAUAUAUUGAAUAGACAGUUUUCCUUCAUUGAACAAAUUAUUUUUUGAGUGCAUAUUUAACUGAUAUUUUGUUAAAAAUUAUCCUCUGCUCUUUUCCUUUUCUAUUUUAAGUUUUAAGCUUCUCAGUGCCAAACCAGGGCUUAUUUAGCCUCGAGAAUGCUGCUUGUAAAAAGAAUCUAGAACUGCACUGUCCAGUAUAGUAGAAGCCAGUUGCCAUAUGUAACUACUAAACUUAAAUUAACUAAAAUUAAAUAAAAUUUAAAAUUCAGUUCCUCAGUCACACAAACUACAUUUCAAGUGCUCAAUAUCAAUAGGUGGCUAGUGGGUACCAAUCUGACAGUGCAGGCAUAGAACAUUUCUAUCAUCACAUAAGUUCUGUUGGACAGUGCUAAUUCUAUUUUUUUAUUUUUAAAUUUUAUUUAUUUUUAUUUUUAUCUGAAACCGAGGACAGUACUGAUUUUCUUUUUUCUUUUUAAAAUUUUUUUAAAAAGAGCUAAUUCUAGAAUGCAGUCAUUAUUCUGUGUCAUAAAGCUGUUUCUGAUAAAGAAAUGAGAGCAUUCAUAUAAUUAUCGUUCUCAUUUUCCUGCCUUGCUGUGGGUACUUGUAUGAAAAUGUAUAAUCUUCUGUUUUCUGUUCAACAAAAAAGCUUUUUAAUACAUAUGUACUUCACAGAUAAUUUCUAUGAUGUAAUUAGUUGUACACAAUUCUCACCAAAUAGAGCAUGCCCAGAAGCCUCUACUAAGCAUCUGCUAUACAAAAGGUCCCAUGGGAGAAACAAAGUUAACUAAGGCAUAGUCUCUGCCAGGAAGGAAACUUAACAUCUAGUAGAAGACACAUUAUUCAUAUUUAAAUAAUAGAAUACAUAUGAAAAUAACCAGAAAAAAUGAAACGAUUACCCAUAAAAAAUUAAAUGUCAGUUCAGAGGAGAGCUCAGUGGUUUAUCAGACUUAAUAAUUCUAAUACAGGAAAACUACUUAAAAUUUUUUUUGAGAAUAUAUUGACUCACAGGUUCCUUUUCCUUUAAUUCUUCCUAGUAAAAUUUUACUAAAUUUUACUUUGGCUUUAUUAUAUCAUGUAUCUUUUCACAGGUUUAGUUUUUCUUCCUGCAUUUUUUUUUUCACCUAUGCUCUUUACUGUUAAGGUAACAAUUUUAAUACAGUCAAUCCUGGCUACCCUUAUAUUAUUGACACCCAAAGUUAAAACACCAAAAUAUUUUAUUUCAAGAUAAAUGUUAUAAUAAUCUGAUUAGGAAAAAUGUAAAUUACCUUAACUUCUACUAUGAGUUUCAUUUUGUCAGUAUCUAGUUUUCUCUUAAGCUGGUCAAUUGCAUGCUGUACCUCAGUGAUCUGGAUUAUUAGGUAAUUCUGUGUGGAUAGAUAGAUAUUUAUUUAGUAUAACAUAUAAACAUUUUUAUUUUUAACUGCCUUGUGAACAUAAACUAUGAAAUGAUAAAGAUCAAAAGAGUAAAUCAUGAAAAUAACCUAUUCCGUAAAGUAAACUAAAUUGCUUUGGAGAAAUUACUAUUUGUUUCUGUUGAUUUCUUGCAUUUUAGGGAACACUUUCUCUAAAGUUACCAUUAAAUUAGCAUCGUAAAAACCAACAACUAUUACUAUGAAAGGAAUAAUAUCUUAGUUAUUAGCAAGACUUUAAAAUUGUCAUAAUGCUUUAUCAGCUGAAUAAGAUUAGAAUUAUUUUAAAAUACUUAAUAAUAUGAUACUAUAUUUUAUAUGCAAAAACUAAUUUAAUACAAGAAAACCUAUUUAAAAUAAGAAGACUUUUUGGUUUUUGUCCAGAAAAGUUUAUGAGUUAUAGUGGUCCUCGCUAAAGAAGUUAUUUAAGAGUUUUAAACUGGCUUUGUGAAAAAAUUCUUAUAUUGAACUGAUUAAACAGUAAGAUAAAGUAUAAGCUAUGCUAAAAAAAAAAGUACCAACUACUAUGGACAAACCAUUACUUGAGCCUAUUUGGACUUUAUAUUAAAUUUAUUUAAAAUAAUAAACUUUUAAUAUUUCAUCUUGUCUAAAGUUAAAUCCUUACUUUUAAUCAUAGUUAACAUAUUUUAAAAUUACUUUUGGAUAAGUGGGAUUGAUCCAACCCAAAUCAAAUUGUUAAAUGCCCUCUUGAAUUUUUUUGUCUGUUAUUUAAUUAUAUGGUGGAAUUAAUAAUAAAAUAAACUUCAUGUCUCUGA